GCAGUUCCCGGGUCCCUCGGCCACCGAAGCCACCCUGCCCUGGUGAAAGGGCUCCCGCACCGCCCGGUGCUCCCCAUCUGCCUGGCGUUGUGCGCAGAGCUGGAAAGCAUGGCUGUUAUAAAUGAAUUCUGAUUUUGGGGAGCAGAUGCCAACUUAGAGCCUCGUACCAAUCUCUCUGUCUUUAAAAGAUGAGGUGACUUGGUGAUUUUCCUGGAAAAUUAUAGAAGCACUGAGGUGGACACUGCGGGUUGUGAGGUUCAGGAGGGGUAAGUGGCUGGCACAAGGUCACAGAGCAGCGCUGCCAUUUGGCUACUUUCCAAUUCAGCAUAGCUGCCCUCUCUGCUGGUGGUAUUCACAGCAUGCAAGAUAAAAUACUCACCAAGGAACAAGUGGCUAACUCCUCACAGAGCUCUCACGGUUUCCUCUUUCCUGACAAAAAGGGAAGCUGGAGGACUGCAGUUUUGCAUCCUAUCCUGCCCUGAGCCUCACUUUGGGCUGUCAGCCAGCCUUGUCUCCAGCCUGCUCACCACUCACUGAUGCUUUUUGCGCCUCUUAGUCAUAACUGCUCAAACAAGGCUCACUCUGAUGAAGAGAAGGGGGUGUAGAAGAGGAAUUAUCAAGGUGUCAUUCUGGUAUUUCAUCUUGGGAAACCAGAAACCUACCAAACAGCAAGGGUUUGCAUACUGGAAGACUCCUCAGCCUGCCCCAGAAGGUCAGCAUUCCUUCCCUCUCAACUAGUUCUGUACAGCUGGAGGAAACAUAAGGUGUUAGAAAGUUUCAGCUAUGGUUUUGGGUUUAGCUUUUAGGAUUUUAGGAGAUUCUAGGCCUUUUGAAAGAAAAAUGAGAUAGUAAGAUCGAAUGGCUGCCUUUGACAUAUUUGAUUUAAUCACAACAAAGGAAAUUGCCUGGCGUUAAGGAACCUGUUAUUUAUCCCUCAGAGGCUCUCCAGCAGAGAACCCAGGCCCUUCACCAUACUGGUGCAUGGUUCCUGCCACUUGUGCAGUCCAUUCCGAAGUUUCUUACAGAUGAGAAUAUUAAUGAAACUUUAUCAUCUUGGUGAGAAAAGCAUUCUAAUAGCUUUAUUCUGACAUACGGAGGUAUGGAGAGCUUGAAGGAGUCAGAGAGGUGCCCAGCUAAGACCUGAAUGCCAUCACCCUCCCCAGGGCUCUGCAGUUUUCUCGUGGUGAACCCUUGAUGGAUUUGUUGUUGCUUGAGAAAUGGCGAUGAUCGAAUUGGGGUUUGGAAGACAGAAUUUUCAUCCAUUAAAGAGGAAGAGUUCAUUGCUGUUGAAACUCAUAGCUGUUGUCUUUGCUGUGCUUCUAUUUUGUGAAUUUUUAAUCUAUUACUUAGCGAUCUUUCAGUGUAAUUGGCCUGAAGUGAAAACCACAGCCUCUGAUGGUGAACAGACCACACGUGAGCCUGUGCUCAAAGCCAUGUUUUUGGCUGACACCCAUUUGCUUGGGGAAUUCCUAGGCCACUGGCUGGACAAAUUACGAAGGGAAUGGCAGAUGGAGAGAGCGUUCCAGACAGCUCUGUGGUUGCUGCAGCCGGAAGUCGUCUUCAUCCUGGGGGAUAUCUUUGAUGAAGGGAAGUGGAGCACCCCUGAGGCCUGGGCGGAUGAUGUGGAGCGGUUUCAGAAAAUGUUCAGACACCCAAGUCAUGUACAGCUGAAGGUAGUUGCUGGAAACCAUGACAUUGGCUUCCAUUAUGAGAUGAACACAUACAAAGUAGAACGCUUUGAGAAAGUGUUCAGCUCUGAAAGACUGUUUUCUUGGAAAGGCAUUAACUUUGUGAUGGUCAACAGCGUGGCGCUGAACGGGGAUGGCUGUGGCAUCUGCUCUGAAACAGAAGCAGAGCUCAUUGAAGUUUCUCACAGACUGAACUGCUCCCGAGAGCAGGCACGUGGCUCCAGCCGGUGUGGACCUGGGCCUCUGCUGCCCACGUCUGCCCCUGUCCUCCUGCAGCAUUAUCCUCUGUAUCGGAGAAGUGAUGCUAACUGUUCUGGGGAAGACGCUGCUCCUGCAGAGGAAAGGGACAUCCCAUUUAAGGAGAACUAUGACGUGCUUUCACGGGAGGCAUCACAAAAGCUGCUGUGGUGGCUCCAGCCGCGCCUGGUUCUCAGUGGCCACACGCACAGCGCCUGCGAGGUGCACCACGGGGGCCGAGUCCCCGAGCUCAGCGUCCCAUCUUUCAGUUGGAGGAACAGAAACAACCCCAGUUUCAUCAUGGGUAGCAUCACGCCCACAGACUACACCCUCUCCAAGUGCUACCUCCCACGUGAGGAUGUGGUUUUGAUCAUCUACUGUGGAGUGGUGGGCUUCCUUGUGGUCCUCACACUCACUCACUUUGGGCUUCUAGCCUCACCUUUUCUUUCUGGUUUGAACUUGCUCGGAAAGCGUAAGACAAGAUGAAGAGCAGGCGCCAUUAUAAAUAUCAAAGCCCAAGAAAUGGAACUUUGGGCAGAGAUCAUGUUAGAAUCAAGUGGAUGAUGAGACCAAUUACAGGCCGUCUCUCUGCACAGCACAGAAAUUCUCAAUCACUGAAAUGAGUAACUGCAAAAUAAAUAGUUGAUUGUACUGUUCUCAUGCUAUAAAAGUGGACAGGUACUCUACAACAAAUCUGUUUUCUCAUUUUUAUCAAAUAUAUGUAUCAUCAAAGGUUGCAUCUGUACAGUAUGUAAAUGCUAUUAAUGUCGUCACUCACAUGCACGACAGUCCUUGUUCCCCCAGGAAGGGCCUGGUGGCCCCAGCACACACUUGGGAUUAUGUGUAUACAUAAAUAAAUAUUGGGCUGUUUCCCUCUUCCUGUGAAGUGGUUCUCAAAUUCCUAUGUACUGUAAAGCUGUACCCUUAAAAGUACAGAUGUGGCCGGGCACAGUGGCUCACACCUGUAAUCCCAGCACUUUGGGAGGCUGAGGCGGGUGGAUCACUUGAGGUCAGGAGUUCAAGACCAGCCUGGCCAACAUGGUGAAACCUCGUCUCCGCUAGAAAUACAAAAAUUAGCCAAGCAUGGUAGCAAGUGCCUAUAAUACCAGCUGAGGCUGAGGCAGGAGAAUCCCUUGAGCCCGGGAGGCGGAGGUUGCAGUGAGCCAAGAUCAUGCCACUGCACUCCAGCCUGGGCAACAGAGUGAGACUCCGUCUCAAAAAAUAUAUUUAAAAAAAAAAAAGUACAGAUGUGAUGUGCAGAACAUAUUGUUUUCGUAGAUUUUUAUACUUGAUCAAUUAAUGGAAUCAGAUUUUUAGAUAAGUGUAAUUUUCUCUAUAGGAGACCACGUUGCUACAUCUGUUAAUGCCUGUCAGUGAUCAAAAGAAACUUAAAAAGUGGAAUGGGAUAUGGCUUUUGGUACCUGAAAAUAAAUGCUUUAAUAAUUGUAAGCCAGAUAAAAGUUAUUCUUUUUGUUUUUUUUCUUAACAGUCUGGCUGUUGUUUGAAUUAAACUCUUAAACAGGAUGUUUAGUUAGAGGGUAAUUGUUGAGUAAUGAUGCAUACAACAGCAUACUUCCCUUUCUUGCUGGGGGUGCAGCUUUUCAGUUUUCUUGUUUUACUUUGACAGUGCAAGGGGAACUGAAAAUAAUUUCCAUUGUAUUAUUUAUCUUAGUUCAGCUGAGGGCUUUAUGAGACAGUGGAUGGGGAGGCAGUAAGACGGUGAUGAGAUAAAAUGUGUGUGUUGCACUGACUGUCUAUAAAGUUAUCCUUUCUUCAUGAAAAAGUAGCAUUUAAAUCUGGAUGAGUUUAUAAAGGAUUACAAAAUGCUGAUUUAUAGAGUAAACUUUAAAAUAUUAAAGACUAAAGACUAAAAGAAGAGUAAUAAUGAAGUAAUGUAGGCUGUCACUUCUCUAGAUUUGUAUUGUUGAAAAUUUAACUUUGGACAUCUUUAUAGAUUAUUAUUUUAGACCUACAAAAACUACCCUCAACUCUGUGGCUACAGCUAGAAUAUGAAGCAUCAUUGCUACACCAGUUCUUACUUUCUAGAUAUUGUUGGUGUGUCAUAAUGUUUGAGGCUGUAUUUGUAAGUCUUGCAAGUGUGAGAAAGAGCCGUAUCUUUUGACUUUAUACUUCAGAUUAAGGUUUUGUAAUGUUUCUUCUUCAAAAGGCAAGUGAAGCUGUCAUCCUCAUUCUCCUAGGCCAGACACAAACAUUGACACGUCAAGGUUUUUUUUUUUUUUUUUUUUGGCCUGAGUCUCACUUUGAUGUCCAGGCUGGAGUGCGAUGGCACGACCUCGGCUCACUGCAAU